AUCAGUCAGGAGGCCGUGCAGUCCGAGAUGGGCUCGUCUCGGGCACCCUGGAUGGGGCGUGUGGGUGGGCACGGGAUGAUGGCACUGCUGCUGGCUGGUCUCCUCCUGCCAGGGACCUUGGCUAAGAGCAUUGGCACCUUCUCAGACCCUUGUAAGGACCCCACGCGUAUCACCUCCCCUAACGACCCCUGCCUCACUGGGAAGGGUGACUCCAGCGGUUUCAGUAGCUACAGUGGCUCCAGCAGUUCUGGCAGCUCCAUUUCCAGUGCCAGAAGCUCUGGUGGUGGCUCCAGUGGUAGCUCCAGCGGAUCCAGCAUUGCCCAGGGUGGUUCUGCAGGAUCUUUUAAGCCAGGAACGGGGUAUUCCCAGGUCAGCUACUCCUCCGGAUCUGGCUCUAGUCUACAAGGUGCAUCCGGUUCCUCCCAGCUGGGGAGCAGCAGCUCUCACUCGGGAAACAGCGGCUCUCACUCGGGAAGCAGCAGCUCUCAUUCGAGCAGCAGCAGCAGCUUUCAGUUCAGCAGCAGCAGCUUCCAAGUAGGGAAUGGCUCUGCUCUGCCAACCAAUGACAACUCUUACCGCGGAAUACUAAACCCUUCCCAGCCUGGACAAAGCUCUUCCUCUUCCCAGACCUUUGGGGUAUCCAGCAGUGGCCAAAGCGUCAGCUCCAACCAGCGUCCCUGUAGUUCGGACAUCCCCGACUCUCCCUGCAGUGGAGGGCCCAUCGUCUCGCACUCCGGCCCCUACAUCCCCAGCUCCCACUCUGUGUCAGGGGGUCAGAGGCCUGUGGUGGUGGUGGUGGACCAGCACGGUUCUGGUGCCCCUGGAGUGGUUCAAGGUCCCCCCUGUAGCAAUGGUGGCCUUCCAGGCAAGCCCUGUCCCCCAAUCACCUCUGUAGACAAAUCCUAUGGUGGCUACGAGGUGGUGGGUGGCUCCUCUGACAGUUAUCUGGUUCCAGGCAUGACCUACAGUAAGGGUAAAAUCUACCCUGUGGGCUACUUCACCAAAGAGAACCCUGUGAAAGGCUCUCCAGGGGUCCCUUCCUUUGCAGCUGGGCCCCCCAUCUCUGAGGGCAAAUACUUCUCCAGCAACCCCAUCAUCCCCAGCCAGUCGGCAGCUUCCUCGGCCAUUGCAUUCCAGCCAGUGGGGACUGGUGGGGUCCAGCUCUGUGGAGGCGGCUCCACGGGCUCCAAGGGACCCUGCUCUCCCUCCAGUUCUCGAGUCCCCAGCAGUUCUAGCAUUUCCAGCAGCUCCGGUUUACCCUACCAUCCCUGCGGCAGUGCUUCCCAGAGCCCCUGCUCCCCACCAGGCACCGGCUCCUUCAGCAGCAGCUCCAGUUCCCAAUCCAGUGGCAAAAUCAUCCUUCAGCCUUGUGGCAGCAAGUCCAGCUCUUCUGGUCACCCUUGCAUGUCUGUCUCCUCCUUGACACUGACUGGGGGCCCCGAUGGCUCUCCCCAUCCUGAUCCCUCCGCUGGUGCCAAGCCCUGUGGCUCCAGCAGUGCUGGAAAGAUCCCCUGCCGCUCCAUCCGGGAUAUCCUAGCCCAAGUGAAGCCUCUGGGGCCCCAGCUAGCUGACCCUGAAGUUUUCCUACCCCAAGGAGAGUUACUCAACAGUCCAUAAGAAGUCAACUGUUGUGUGUGUGCAUGCCUUGGGCACAAACAAGCACAUACACUAUAUCCCAUAUGGGAGAAGUCCAGUGCCCAGGCAUAGGGUUAGCUCAGUUUCCCUCCUUCCCAAAAGAGUGGUUCUGCUUUCUCCACUACCCCAAGGUUGCAGACUCUCUCUUAUCACCCCUUCCUCCUUCCUCUUCUCAAAAUGGUAGAUUCAAAGCUCCUCUCUUGAUUCUCUCCUACUGUUUAAAUUCCCAUUCCACCACAGUGCCCCUCAGCCAGAUCACCACCCCUUACAAUUCCCUCUACUGUGUGGAAAUGGUCCAUUGAGUAACACCCCCAUCAGCUUCUCAACUGGGAAACCCCUGAAAUGCUCUCAGAGCACCUCUGACGCCUGAAGAAGUUAUACCUUCCUCUUCCCCUUUACCAAAUAAAGCAAAGUCAAACCAUCAUCUGGAAACAGUGGCCACUUUUCACUGACCUUUCUUCGACAUCUAGUCAACCCACCCAAUAUGCCACUGGGCUCUCGCUCCCAAUUCCACCCCACCCUCCAUUACAGAGCUCACCACGCCCUCCUAGAUCACCGUCCCCAACACACCCAUUGCCUCUCAAGGCCCUUAUCUCAGCCCCUUCCUGUGGCCACUUCCCUCAGUGCUCAGAUGAUUCCCUGGGUGAGGGAGACACUGGGGCACCCUCAGAGGUUGAAGCAGGCUCCCUGCUGUCCCUGGAUCCUGGACAGAUGGCUCAGUAAACUGUGGGGACUAGGUGCAGACUUUUUGCCUUCUUGGAGUCCUGGGUCUCCUCUGAGAGUCUGGGUGGUGCUCUUCCUACGCCUCUAGAGGUCUCUGUGUUCCUCAUUUUCCUUCAAAAGCGGGCUGUGUUUCUCUUCUACCUUCCAGCUGCUCCCACAGAGGAGGAAGACAAUAAAUAUUUGUUGAACUGAAAGCA